AUCCACAUCCGCAUCGUCGUCCUCCCCGACCGCGUCCUGCAGCAGCUGCCAGUGGAGCCGCCUGACAAGGACUGCCAUCCACCAUGGUGAAGCUGGGCUGCAGCUUCUCUGGGAAGCCAGGUAAAGACCCUGGGGACCAGGAUGGGGCUGCCAUGGACAGUGUGCCUCUGAUCAGCCCCUUGGACAUCAGCCAGCUCCAGCCGCCACUCCCUGACCAGGUGGUCAUCAAGACACAGACAGAAUACCAGCUGUCCUCCCCAGACCAGCAGAAUUUCCCUGACCUGGAGGGCCAGAGGCUGAACUGCAGCCACCCAGAGGAAGGGCGCAGGCUGCCCACCGCACGGAUGAUCGCCUUCGCCAUGGCGCUACUGGGCUGCGUGCUGAUCAUGUACAAGGCCAUCUGGUACGACCAGUUCACCUGCCCCGACGGCUUCCUGCUGCGGGGCCCUGAGUUCUGAACUGGAGGCUGAUCUUCGGUGUCCUGAAGCCAUGGCUCCAUUACAAACUGUCCGCAGUGUCCCCAACCGCAGAAGCGGGAGGGCCUGGGCCCGGGGCGCACAGGAGGGCUCAGCCCCACCGACCCUGACCCGGCCCCUCCCGCAGCACAAGAUCUGCACGCCGCUGACCCUGGAGAUGUACUACACGGAGAUGGACCCCGAGCGCCACCGCAGCAUCCUGGCGGCCAUCGGGGCCUACCCGCUGAGCCGCAAGCACGGCACGGAGACGCCGGCGGCCUGGGGGGACGGCUACCGCGCAGCCAAGGAGGAGCGCAAGGGGCCCACCCAGGCUGGGGCGGCGGCGGCGGCCACCGAACCCCCCGGGAAGCCGUCGGCCAAGGCGGAGAAGGAGGCGGCGCGGAAGGCGGCCGGGAGCGCGGCGCCCCCGCCCGCGCAGUGACGUCUCCAGCCCCGCAGCCCGGCCCGGGCGUCCUCCGCCAGCUCCUGUGACCAGCGCGUCUCCCGAUGCUCUCCGCCGUGUUCGUGUCCCCAGGCGCCCUCGCUGCAGCCCCGCCCCCGUGGGUCUCUGACUCUGUCGCUUUUCUCUAAGUAAAGAUUUCACGUCCACCGGAGGCUUCCAUCUCUCCUGCGCGUCCUCUGCCGGGCUGGCCUUUCUCCCGCCCCCCACCCCGCCAGUUGUGAGUGAGGCCGGCAUUGUGCUCCCCCCAGGGACCCCCGAAGGACCCAGGAGAGACCCCGUGGGGGGCAGCUCCCAGGAAGCCGUGGUGCGCCCAGGCGGAGCACGCGCAUCCUCGCGCUGCGUGGUCCGGGCCUUGUCCAAGCCCCACCGGGAUGUGCCUUAAUGGCGGGGCUCCGGCCCACCCAGGGGAGCCUCGGGUCCAUCCCUAUCCGCUGCCCAGCCCCUUGUCCUGCUGGUUCCCCGACCCCCCGCCCCCAUCUACCUGGUGCUGGGCCUGGGCCCCGGGCGUUCCCCCUCUGACAGGAGUGUCUGCCUCCCGGGGGACCCCUGGUUCUGGGCGGCACCCAUGAGCAGCUCCUGCCUCCUAGAUGUGUGGCCCACAGGCAUAAAUGACCAAGUGAAGAAAGGAGUGAAUGGGGGCGUCUGAGUGGGGAGUGGGGCCUGAUGAGGGGUGAGCUCUGGUUCCUGGGGGCUGGGGUCUCCCGUGUCCCUGGAGCCAGAUGAAAGAUGGUGAGGCUGAAACGCCAGGGGAGCCUGGAGCUGCCAUGAGUCUCCCCCAGCAUCCCCACCCCAGCCCCAGCAUCCCCACCCCAGCCCCAGCAUCCCCACCCCAGCCCCAGCCAACUCCCGGCACUGAACACUACAGGGAAUGGACUUCCGGCAGAUCUCACCCACCACCUGCACCACCCCAGCCAGCAGCAGCUCUGCAGCCCCGCCCACCCCAGCCAGCAGCAGCUCUGCAGCCCCGCCCACCCCAGCCAGCAGCAGCUCUGCAGCCCCGCCCACCCCAGCCAAUUGCAGCACUGCAGCCCCGCCCACCCCAGCCAAUUGCAGCACUGCAGCCCCGCCCACCCCAGCCAGCAGCGGCUCUGCAGCCCCGCCCACCCCAGCCCCCGACCAUUGGUGGAUGGAAGCCCCCCACCAUUGGCUCCCAGGCUUGCUGGCUAGGUGCGGGUCUAGGCAGCUUCCCAGCUCAGUGGGACUGGCCUGCUUUGGAACAGCGGCAGUGCCCAGGAAGCCUGUGAACUGGGCCUGCCAGGGAAGCCAUGGUGAGCUGGAAGCCAGCCAGGUGGGGUCAGGGAAGGCAGGGCCAUGCACACCACACCCUUCACUGCUGGGCUUCUAAGGGCAUUGGCCAGAUGAACAAGCACACGCAGAACUGAAUUGGCCCUGAUGGCCUGCAAGGGAGGGGGGCCCGGGGCCUGGGGCGUCAGCUGGGAUAUAUGGGGGCAGGGAGUCUCUGCAUGGCCGAUGUUUGAAUUAAAAUACAGCUUUCCCCUGUA